GCCGCCGCCGGGCCAUGGCCGCGCAGCUGCUGGAGGAGAAGCUGACCUGCGCCAUCUGCCUGGGGCUCUACCAGGACCCAGUGACGCUGCCCUGCGGCCACAACUUCUGCGGGGCCUGCAUCCGGGACUGGUGGGACCGCUGCGGAAAGGCGUGCCCCGAGUGCCGGGAGCCCUUUCCCGACGGCGCCGAGCUGCGCCGCAACGUGGCCCUCAGCGGCGUGCUGGAGGUGGUGCGCGCCGGGCCCGCCCGGGAUCCCGGCCCCGAUCCCGGCCCCGGCCCCGACCCUGCCGCGCGCUGCCCCCGCCACGGGCGGCCGCUGGAGCUCUUCUGCCGGACCGAGGGCCGCUGUGUGUGCAGCGUGUGCACCGUGCGCGAGUGUCGCCUCCACGAGCGGGCGCUGCUGGAUGCCGAGCGCCUCAAGCGCGAGGCCCAGCUGAGAGCCAGCCUGGAGGUUACCCAGCAGCAGGCCACCCAGGCCGAAGGCCAGCUACUAGAGCUGCGCAAGCAAAGCAGCCAGAUCCAGGGCCCUGGCCACCCUGAAGCCCCUCCUGUUCCCGCCCAGAACUCGGCCUGCAUCUUGGCCUCCUGGGUCUCCGGCAAGUUCAGCAGCCUGCUACAGGCCCUGGAAAUACAGCACACGACAGCACUGAGGAGCAUCGAGGUGGCCAAGACGCAGGCGCUGGCACAGGCUCGAGACGAGGAGCAGCGGCUGCGGGUCCAUUUGGAGGCUGUGGCUCGCCAUGGCUGCAGGAUCCGGGAGCUCCUGGAGCAGGUGGAUGAGCAGACCUUCCUGCAGGAAUCGCAGCUCCUCCAGCCCCCAGGGCCUCUUGGGCCACUGACCCCUCUGCAGUGGGAUGAAGACCAACAGCUGGGUGACCUGAAGCAGUUGCUAAGCCGGCUGUGUGGCCUCCUCUUGGAAGAGGGGAGCCACCCUGGGGCACCAGCCAAGCCUGUGGACUUAGCCCCCGUGGGUAAGACUGACCCCAGGCCUCCCCCUGCUGUCCUGGGUCCAGCUGCCCCUCCCGCUGGGGGGGUGGAGGCGGGUCAGGGCCCACACAUCGUGACCUCUCCAACCAUUCCCUUAACACUGCUUUGCCCCCUAGAGGCCCCAGGUCCCCUGGCACCGGUCCCAAGCACAGUUUGUCCACUGAGGAGGAAACUCUGGCAGAAUUAUCGCAAUCUGACCUUUGAUCCAGUCAGCGCCAACCGUCACUUCUAUCUGUCGCGCCAGGACCAGCAGGUGAAGCACUGUCGUCAGUCCCGGGGCCCAGGCGGGCCCGGCAGCUUUGAGCUCUGGCAGGUGCAAUGUGCCCAGAGCUUCCAGGCCGGGCACCACUACUGGGAGGUGCGCGCGUCAGACCACUCGGUGACACUGGGCGUCUCCUACCCGCAACUGCCACGGUGCAGGCUGGGGCCCCACACAGACAACAUUGGCCGGGGACCCUGCUCCUGGGGGCUCUGCGUCCAGGAGGACAGCCUCCAGGCCUGGCACAACGGGGAAGCCCAGCGCCUCCCAGGGGUGUCAGGGCGGCUCCUGGGCAUGGAUUUGGACCUGGCCUCAGGCUGCCUCACCUUCUACAGCCUGGAGCCCCAGACCCAGCCCCUGUACACCUUCCAUGCCCUCUUCAACCAGCCCCUCACCCCCGUCUUCUGGCUCCUCGAGGGUAGGACCCUGACCCUGUGCCAUCAGCCAGGGGCUGUGUUCCCUCUGGGGCCCCAGGAAGAGGUGCUCAGCUGAAGAAGGCAUGGGAUGGAGCCCUGGCAUAGCUGCCACCAUGCCUAUGUGCCCAAGAGCUGCCCAGCUUCAGCUUGGGGACUGGAGGACCAGCUGUUGGCCUCUCUGUUAACUCAGAAAGAGAUGGGAGGUUGGGGGAGGUGAGCAUAAACGCAGAGUUCACUGUUGCAGCCUUUUUGAAGGGGACACAGUCUAGGAGGGGGAUAAAUGGGAUGCCCUUGCCCCAGAGAGAACCCAGUUCUAGGUACUGUCUGGGCCUGGGAGGCGAGAGCAGUGCCCAGGGGACUUCUGGGCUUACAGGACAGCGUGUGUGACAAAAUUCAGAUCUACCUGAACUUGCCUCUGGAGAUGAUAAGGGCCAAAGGAGCAGUCAGGGAGGGGCGGUGAGCCAGAGUAGUCCCAGGGGGAGACAGAUUCCUCCCUCCUCCCCGCCUGCAGCUCUCUUUAAUUUUUUGUAACAUUUGGAGAGACGUCCGUCCUGUCUUGUAGUCUUUUUAUUUUGUGCAUCCUUAUAAUUGUAUUCUACAAACAAUUUUGUUUUCUGCAUUUAAACAUUUUUGUGUUUUUAGGAGAUGGUCUUGCUCUGUCACUCAGGCUGGAGUACAGUGGCACAAUCAUGGCUCACUGCAGCCUCGAGCUCCUGAGCUCAAAGGAUCCUCCCACCUCAGCCUCCAGAGUAGCUCAGAUUACAGUGUUUUCUGAAGUUUCCUGACUUAACAUAAGCAUUUUUCACAUGAUUGAAAAUUUUCACUGAUUGCUGUAGUCAUUCUAAUGACUAUCAAGUUUAUUUAUCCAUUAUUGGACAUUUAAAUUUCUUUCUUUUUAGCUAUACAAACAUUGAUGUGUUUUUUUUGAGACAGGAUCUCCAUCUGUCACCCAGGCUGGUGUGCAGGGGUGCGGUCAUGGGCUCAUGGGAUUCUCCUACCUCAGCCUCCUGAGUAGCUGGGAUUACAGGUGUAUGCCACCACGCCUGGCUUAUGAUGAAUAUUUCUGAGUGGGAUGUUUGGCCACAUUUAUGGUCAUGUAUGUAGGCUGUUACCUCAAGUGAGUCACUCAGGGAACAAUGAGCACUUGAAGAUUUUUUUAUACAAAAGGCCACAGUGAGGCCACCUUGAGUCAAGCCGACUAAGGCCCCUCAACCCUGUCACUAAGCAGCACGUGACACUGGCAGGACCUUCAUCUCCAGCAUCCCACCCCUGGGUGUGGGACUUUGGGGCAGCCGUGUGUGCAGGUGUCGGCACAGGCUAGCUCCUCCUGGUUUGGUGUGGUGUUUGCCAUUGCAGAGCAAGCUGCCACGAAGACCCCUGGGCAUGAUUUUGCUUGUAUUUCCGGAAGUGGGGUUGCUGGGUCAUAGGGCAGGUGUAAUUUUUUUUACUUGAAAUGUUCCACUUCUUGUUCUGGGAGGUGGUUCCAAGGGUGUCUGCUUUUGGCCAGGCGCAGUGGCUCACGCUUGUAAUCCCAGCACUUUGGGAGGCCGAGGCAGGCGGAUCACAAGGUCAGGAGUUCGAGACCAGCCUGGCCAACAAGGCAAAACCCCGUCUCUACUAAAAAUACAAAAAUUAGCCGGGCAUGGUGGUGUGCGCCUGUAAUCCCAGCUACUGGGGAGGCUGAGGCAGAAGAAUCGCUUGAACCCAGGAGGUGAGGUUGCAGUGAGCUGAGAUUGCACCACUGGACUACAGCCUGGGUGACAGAGCGAGACUCUGUCUCAAAAAAAAAAAAAAAAAGGGAGGGCUGUCUGCUUUUUGUAACUUGAAAAACUGGACAUCUAUGUUAUAUGUACUCAUGGAUAAAUAUUUCACAAUAAAACUUUUUAAAAGGA